GGUCUCAGGGCAGGGCUGGAGCAGAGAGGCCCCUAUGUGGCAGCCGGCCUUCAGUCUUGUUCCUCCAAGCAAGUGGGGUGGAGAUGUUGGGGUCCUUUGGCUGGAUGCCACUAUCUGUUGAAUCUGACAAAAUAAUUUUCUUUUUUUUUUUUGAGACAAGAGUCUCACUGUGUCGCGCAGGCUGGAGUGCAGUGGCGCAGUCUCGGCUCACUGCAAGCUCCGCCUCCCGGGUUCACGCCAUUCUCCUGCCUCAGCCUCCCGAGUAGCUGGGGCUACAGGCACCCGCCACCACGCCUGGCUAAUGUUUGUAUUUUUAGUAGAGACGGGGUUCCACCAUGUUGGCCAGGAUGCUCUCAAUCUCUUGACCUCAUGAUCCGCCCGCCUUGGCCCCCCACAGUGCUGGGGUUACAGCUGUGAGCCACCGCGCCUGGCUCUGCCAAAAUAAUUUUAUUAGAGAACUUGAGGGCAGUGCCCAGAAUUGAAGGCGAAGCCCCAGAAGCAUGUUUUGCAGAGAAGUGCCCAGGGAAGCUCUGAGGGCCCAUGUAGCAAAGAUCAGGGGAUAGUCGGUCUGAGGGUGAAUGGGCCACUCGGACCAAGACCCCAGUCUUGGGGGAGGGCUUAGCUGGAGCAGGUCCUGGCACAGUUGACUGAUGGUGCACAGAACCCGUGCAUCCCACGGCCCCACGGUGCUGCAGCUGCAGGAGGGGCGGAGGCUGCAGCCAGACAGCAUCAGAAGCCAGCGUGGUUCUGGAAGGAUCGAGAACACCAAGGUGUUAGGGCUGCAGCAGGGGUCCUGUCCCCUGGCACCCCUCACCGCCCUAAUCUUUUACCCUUAGGAGGCAGCAGACACGAGGGGCUGCCCGAGGCUCUAGGGCGGCCAGUGAGGCAGGAAACAUGUUCCAGCCCCAGCUAGGUACUGGUCCGUGGACCCACCUCCCAGAAAGCCCAUCACUGUGUAAUCGUCUAACCUGGGGCUCGCCGAGGCCUAUGCCUUGAGUCCACCCAAAUAGGGGAUGUGAUGUUUGGAGCUGCAGCAGCCGCCCUACGGUUGGGAGUCAGAGAAGAGCCGGUGUUCCAGGGACAAUGCAGCAGAGGCUGAGCCCAGGCCUGCUGUCCUGAGAGGUGGCUGGAUCACUGACACUUUGGCAGUGGUGCUGGGGUUUAUGUCAUGACCUGCAGCUGAGCCUACUUCCAAUGACCGUGAGAUCUGAAAGACUGUUUUGAGGGCGUAGCCUCUGCCAUGAUUGUGGGGAAUGCUGUCCUGUUUCCUCCCUUGGCCCUGCUCAGCCCAGCGAGAGGCUGAGGCGCACGUGGCUCCCCGGGUGCCCACAGGCAGCGUGGCUCACCAGCCGGGCCCUUUUCCACUGAGCCAGAACCCCCCAAAGCCUUCAAUGCAGGCACCACGGUGAGCCCACGAGAAACCCUGCUUGCCACCUCCCACACCCCCACCCCCAAGUUCAAAGGAAAUGGUCCCUGAACCAAGGGCUGAGAUCAGCUGUGGGUCCAGCUGUCCUGGGGAGCUGUACUGGAGCCCACCACGGUGGGACUGUUGGUCCGGCGGUGACCCCCACCUCCAUGUCUGUGGCCGCAGCUGGACAGGCCACUCCCUGGGCCACAGAGAUGUUUUACCUCUCGCAGCCCUCGGGCACACAUUGAGCAGAUGUGUGUGUGUGUGCGUGUGUGGGUGGGUGCGCAUUUGUGUGUGCCUGUGUGUGUGCGCAUGUGGUGUGGGUGCACGUGUGUGCACGUGUGUGGGUAAACAUUGUGUGUGCGCAUACGUGUGUGGGUAAACAUUUGUAUGUGCACGCGUGUGUGGGUAAACGUGUGUGCGCACGUAUGUAUGUGUGUACAUUUGUAUGUGUGUACAUUUGUAUGCAUGUGUGCCUGUGUGUGUGUGCCUGUGUGUGUGGGUGCACAUUUGUGUGUGUGUGUGUGCCUGUGUGUGUGUGUGCACGUAUGUAUGUGUGCACACUUGUAUGCAUGUGUGCCUGUGUGUGUGGGUGCACAUUUGUGUGUGUGUGCCUGUGUGUGUGGGUGCACAUUUGUGUGUGUGGGUGCACAUUUGUGUGUGUGUGCGCCUGUGUGGGUGCACAUUUGUGUGUGUGUGUGCCUGUGUGUGUGCCUGUGUGUGUGGGUGCCUGUGUGUGUGGGGCACAUUUGUGUGUGUGUGUGCCUGUGUGUGGGUGCACAUUUGUGUGUGUGCCUCUGUGUGUGUGCCUGUGUGUGGGGGUGCACAUUUGUGUGUGCGCCUGUGUGUGGGGGUGCACAUUUGUGUGUGCGCCUGUGUGUGUGGGUGCACAUUUGUGUGUGUGUGCGCCUGUGUGUGUGGGUGCCUGUGUGUGUGUGGGGCACAUUUGUGUGUGUGUGUGUGCCUGUGUGUGGGUGCACAUUUGUGUGUGUGCCUGUGUGUGUGUGCCUGUGUGUGGGGGUGCACAUUUGUGUGUGUGUGUGCCUGUGUGUGGGGGUGCACAUUUGUGUGUGUGUGUGCCUGUGUGUGUGGGUGCACAUUUGUGUGUGUGUGUGCCUGUGUGUGUGGGUGCACAUUUGUGUGUGUGUGCCUGUGUGUGUGGGUGCACAUUUGUGUGUGUGUGUGCCUGUGUGUGUGGGUGCACAUUUGUGUGUGUGCCUGUGUGUGGGUGCACAUUUGUGUGUGUGUGCCUGUGUGUGUGUGCCUGUGUGUGUGGGUGCACAUUUGUGUGUGUGUGUGCCUGUGUGUGUGGGUGCACAUUUGUGUGUGUGUGUGUGCCUGUGUGUGUGUUGCAGGCCCUGGAUGCCAGACACUGAAUAAACGCAGGAAGACGUCUGUCUUCAUUCUCCUCGUGGGUCGCUGGUCCAGAAACACCUGGAUGGAAAGUGCUCUGCAGGAACGGUGCCUCUGCCUGUGGCGGGGACCCUGCACAGACGCAGUCUUCAGCAAGGAAGUGCUGGGAACGCCCUGGAGUGAACCCAGGAAGAUGCCUGCAGUGGGUGCCAGGGCCCCUCUCCACCGUCCCUGCUGGGCUUCGGGGCCACGCCCGACUGCUGUGAACGGCCUGCGGAGCACCACGUGCGACGGCUGGAGGCGAGAGAGAAAAGCUCCAUUCUUCCCAGGACCUCAGCGCAGCCCUGGCCCAGGAAGGCAGGAGACAGAGGCCAGGACGGUCCAGAGGUGUCGAAAUGUCCUGGGGACCUGAGCAGCAGCCACCAGG